AUCCUCCUGGCAAGCUUCAAUAUAGCUGUGGAAGUCUGCAGUCUACAAGAGCCUACUAUAGACAUUCUACAACCAAGCAGAAUCAUGGAACAGCCGACUUCAAGCACCAAUGGGGAGAAGAGGAAGAGCCCCUGUGAAUCCAAUAACAAAAAAAAUGAUGAGAUGCAGGAGGCACCGAACAGGGUCUUAGCCCCCAAACAGAGCUUGCAAAAGACAAAAACAAUAGAAUAUCUAACAAUAAUAGUGUAUUACUACAGGAAGCAUACGAAAAUAAAUUCAAAUCAACUGGAGAAGGACCAGUCCCGAGAGAACUCCAUCAAUCCAGUCCAAGAGGAGGAGGACGAAGGCCUAGACUCAGCUGAAGGAUCUUCACAGGAGGACGAAGACCUGGACUCAUCUGAAGGAUCUUCACAGGAGGACGAAGACCUGGACUCAUCUGAAGGAUCUUCACAGGAGGACGAAGACCUGGACUCAUCUGAAGGAUCUUCACAGGAGGACGAAGACCUGGACUCAUCUGAAGGAUCUUCACAGGAGGACGAAGACCUGGACCCACCUGAAGGAUCUUCACAGGAGGACGAAGACCUAGACUCAUCUGAAGGAUCUUCACAGGAGGGUGGGGAGGACUAGUCAAACAUGGAGAAACCAAAUUGGACAAAUCCUCACUACCAAUGGCGAUGAUUACAAUAAAAUCAAGUUUGAGGAGCUGA